GUCCGCGCGCGCCCCCUGCCGGCCGCGCCGGGACCCGCGGCGGCUCUGGCCCAGGCUGGGACGGGGGUGCGGGGUAGGGAGGGCGAUCCGCUCCCGCCGCGGCCCUCUGAGCCCUCAAAACUCCGAAAAACAGGACGGGGUUCGUCAAUGGCUAGAAAAGCCCAAGCGCGCCGCCACCGGGCCCUACACCCCUGGGAGGGCUCCGUGGUGGGCGGGGGCUCAGGGGGCUCUGGGUCCUUGGCGGGCAGCAGGGCACAUGCGCUGCUCGGACCGCCAGCGUCCAGCCGCUGCGCCCAGGGACCGUCAGCACCUCCCGCUUGUGCUGCUCUGCCGUGGUCAACACUGGUCAUUGAACACAAGCCAGAUUCAAGACGACUCCCCGCCCCCCCGCCCCCACACCCCCCGCAGGCUGCGGCAUCUGUGGGUGGGCGCCACAUCCUGGGCUUGGCCUGGGGGAGGGGGAUGACUGCACCCCGCCCUGUGCUCUCACCCAGACGGGCACACACAGCACCUUUAGACGGGUGGGGAGGGGCCCCAACUUAAGAUGCUGCAGGCCAAAGACUAGGAAGCAGAGGGUCCCCCUGCGGGCCCCCUUUCCCGUGCACGUGCUCACACUGUUACACAUGCGUCACCCUGGCUCAGCCUCACACAGAGCUCUGGAGAACUGCGAUUUCUGUCCCCAGAGCUUUGUUGGUUUGCAGGGUGGACCAGGCCCCUCACUAAGCCAGGACUGUGCCCACGAGGGCCAGGGGGAGGGCCAGGUCCAUUUGGAGGGCGCAUGCCAUGUACUUUGUGGUCCCUGGCCUCCCCAGUGUCUCUCCAGAGGGUCCUUCCCUGUUUCUCCAGGAGGCAGCAGGCUGAACACAGAUGCUUUUGAGGGGUGGGUGGGGAACACUCGGGGAAGUCUAGGAUGCUAAGUCCCCAGCAGAGGUUCAGCCUGUGCCCCCGCCACACAGCUCGUGGGCAUCUUGGGGGUUUUUCCUCAGGUCCCUAGAUUGGCCGGUGCUGCUGCCGGGGUCCCACCACCCCUGGGCGGGUGCCGCCGGGGCAAGAUGGUGGCCUUUCUGCCAACGCCCUCCUGCCUGGGGAACUCAGAAAAAACUGAGAGGCCGCACCAUCUGCAUCUGUGAUUAAUUAGCAGUAAUUACACGUGUUGUCAACGGCAGGAGAGUCACAGGUUUGAUGACAUUCCGAGGGCUUUAGGGAAACAAAAACUUGGCCCCACUCUGCCACUGAGGAGCCCCAGAUCGCCAGCCCGUCCAUCCCUCCCUGGCCAGGGGCAGGGCCGGGAGAGGGGCCCAGGUCCCCGAGAGCUUUUGCCCUCCUCUCCAACCCCGUCCUCCUCCAUGUCUGACCUGCAGCCAAGGCUGGGCGGAGCAGGGAUGGAGACACCACCUUAUAUUACAUAACCUCCCUCUGCUCCAAACACCCUUCACCCAUCUUUGGCCCAAAGUCCAGGAUGCCAGCCCGAGGCCCAGAGCCGCGCCUUCUCCACAGGAGACUGGGGCACCCCGGACAGACGUCCCCGUGUGGUGGCACCUGCCCGGGCUCCUUCUUGCCUCCCCUCUCGGGAGGAGAGCCCCUGCCACCCACCCCACCUCCUCCCGCUACGACCUCAGCACGAGCCAGGCCAGGGAUGUCCUCCCAACAGUCCAGCCUCACCCCCCACCCUCGUCCCCUCUGCUUCCCUGAGGGCCCCCCGCAACCUCCGUGAAAGAGGAAGGGUCUCCACCUCCCCCUUCCCUCCGUCAUCCCCCCAAAAGUAUGUACUGGGGGACUCAAGCCCAGCGCAGGGCGGCUCCUGGAGUUCAGCGGGGAGGUGAGCAAACACCUGGCGCCGGAGCUUUCUGAAUUUGGAUGGGCAGGACCCCCGCGAUCCCGCAGAAACCUGUUGAGAGUGUGAGGGGCUGGGCUCCUAAGGGCAGAGCCCGCAUCUCCAAAGUGCCCAAGGGCACCGAGACCACCGCAUAAGUGGGAACCGAGGCGACCCCCGGGAAGCUGCGAGUUCAUGGCGUCCCGGUGCUCCGAGCCCUACCCGGAGGUCUCCAGAAUCCCUACCGUCAGGGGAUGCAACGGCUCCCUGUCUGGUGCCCUCUCCUGCUGCGAGGACUCGGCCCGGGGCUCGGGCCCGCCCAAGGCCCCUACGGUGGCCGAGGGUCCCAGCUCCUGCCUUCGGCGGAACGUGAUCAGCGAGAGGGAGCGCAGGAAGCGGAUGUCGUUGAGCUGUGAGCGUCUGCGGGCCCUGCUGCCCCAGUUCGAUGGCCGGCGGGAGGACAUGGCCUCGGUCCUGGAGAUGUCUGUGCAGUUCCUGCGGCUUGCCAGCGCCCUGGGGCCCAGUCAGGAGCAGCACGCUAUUCUUGCUUCCUCCAAGGAAAUGUGGCACUCGUUGCAGGAGGAUGUUUUACAGUUGACGUUGUCGAGUCAGAUUCAAGCAGGUGUGCCAGACCCUGGGACGGGAGCGUCCAGCGGGACUCGAACCCCAGAUGUGAAGGCGUUUCUGGAAAGUCCUUGGUCCCUGGAUCCAGCGUCGGCCAGCCCAGAGCCCGUGCCGCACAUCCUUGCGUCCUCCAGGCAGUGGGACCCCGCGAGCUGCACGUCCCUGGGCACGGACAAGUGUGAGGCACUGUUGGGGCUGUGCCAGGUGCGGGGUGGGCUGCCCCCUUUCUCAGAACCUUCCAGCCUGGUGCCGUGGCCCCCAGGCCGGAGUCUUCCUAAGGCUGUGAGGCCACCCCUGUCCUGGCCUCCGUUCUCGCAGCAGCAGACCUUGCCCGUGAUGAGCGGGGAGGCCCUUGGCUGGCUGGGCCAGGCUGGGCCCCUGGCCAUGGGGGCUGCACCUCUGGGGGAGCCAGCCAAGGAGGACCCCAUGCUGGCGCAGGAGGCCGGGUCUGCGUUGGGGUCUGAUGUGGACGAUGGGACGUCCUUCCUGCUGACUGCUGGUCCCAGCUCGUGGCCGGGAUUUAGUGUUUGGGAGCCCGUUCCUGGUUCUGGUCCAACAGGUGUCCUGGGUCUGGGGCCACCAGGGUCUCUGGAGGGUCGAGGAGGCAGUGGCCCUGCAUGGGCCCCAGCUGAGAGCAGUCCACUGGAUGUUGGAGAGCCAGGCUUCCUAGGGGACCCUGAGCUUGGCUCCCAGGAGCUCCAGGACAGCCCUCUGGAGCCGUGGGGCCUGGAUGUGGACUGUGCAGGCCUGGCCCUGAAGGACGAGGUGGAGAGCAUCUUCCCUGACUUCUUUGCCUGCUAGCAGCCAGGCUGUGGAGAGGAGGCGGGCGGGGCCGGUGGAUCUGGAGCCGUGUGUGUCCCUGUCGCGUGCUUGGGCAUUUUAUUUUGGGUUUGGGUUGCAGCUGCACCCUAAUUUGAGCGAGGCUUACAGGCUGUGAGAAGAGGAUAGUGAAUAUUAAAGAGGGAAAGCAGUUUUCCUGGAGGAAGCAAAA